GCACCUCCUGACUACUCCCUGCGGGACGGCUGGGUGUGAGGGUGGCAGCCUUGUGCUCAAGCCGAGGCUGGGCUGGAGGAUGGAGAAGGACACGGGGACCACACACAGGAGGCACCGGCCCGGCCUCAGGGCCCUGCCCUCAGGAGUGGCCCUUGGGCACCUCAAGGCGGCCAGUGAGGCCUCUGAACUUCAGCGAAGCAGGAGUCUGGGAGGCCUGCAGCCCGAGGGGGACCCUCCCAGCCGCCCUAGGAAGCCUCACAAGGAGCUGGAGUCCGAAGAUCAAGGGAAAGACCCAAGCAGUAACGCGGAAGAUGCCAGCUGUCAGAAAAACCUAGCACAAGACAAGAAGGAAAGCUUCAGCACCCUUGGGAAGCUGGGUCAUGAGAGUGGAAAACAAGACCCAGAGAGGGAGAAGAGCGACUUGGAGGCCAGCAUGCAGGAGGUGCAGGAAGGCGAGCACGCAGACGGAGGCUUGCAGGAGGCCAAGGAACAGGAGGCAGAGUCCAUAAAGCUAAAUGACCUUCAGGAAGAAGAGAAAGCAUCUGUGUUUGUGGAGAUUGAUCUGGGAGACCAUGCUGAGGAGGUGGUCACCGAUGCCAAGAAGGAAGAGAAGCCGUCCCAGAUGGAUGUGGAAGAUCUGUCAGAAGACGAGAUGCAGACCAGCUGGGUGUGCUGCAUCCCGUACUCCACCAGGAAGAGGGCAAAGGAGAGCACCUAGCGCCCCGGAGAGGGUGCUCAGAGCUUGGCGAAGAAGAGGAAGGAGACGGGGUGCAGAGGGGCUGGGGGCACAGGAGGCGGGACGGAGGGCGAUCCGGCCACCUACUUGCCGCCCAAGAGCCUUCUCUGCCAGGCACUGAGGUUUCUGUUUUCUUCUUGUGGGACUGGCCAGGCCUGGAAGGAGCGAGAGCACAGACUGCGCCUUUGGGCUAAAGAUCCCGCCAGCUCUGAGCAACGCUGGGGUGCCGAUGACCACACCAGGUGUGAGCCACGCCUGAAACCCACUGCCCACUGGGUGAGUGAUGACGUGACCUUCAACAAACACAAUAAACAAGCACGGGAAGAUGCUCCUCCUCUCCACCAGAUGCUCCUCCUCUCCACCAGAUGCUCCUCCUCUCCACCAGAUGCUCCUCCUCUCCACCAGAUACUACUCCUCUCCACCAGAUACUACUCCUCCUCUCCACCAGAUGCUCCUCGUCUCCACCAGAUGCUCCUCCUCUCCACCGGAUGUUCCUCCUCUCGUCGAGAUGCUCCUCGUCUCCUCGAGAUGCUCCUCGUCUCCACCGGGUGCUCCUCGUCUCCACCGGAUGCUCCUUGUCUCCGCCGGAUGCUCCUCCUCUUCGCCAAAUACUACUCCUCCUCUCCGCCAGAUCCUACUCCUCCUCUCCGCCAGAUACUACUCCACCUCUCCGCCAGAUCCUACUCCUCCUCUCCGCCAGAUCCUACUCCUCUCUGCCAGAUCCUACUCCUCCUCUCCGCCAGAUCCUACUCCUCCUCUCUGCCAGAUCCUACUCCUCGUCUCCGCCAGAUGCUCCUCCUCGUCUCCGCCAGAUGCUCCUCGUCUCCGCGAGAUGCUCCUCCUCUCUGCGAGAUGCUCCUCCUCUCCACCGGAUGCUCCUCCUCUCCUCGAGAUGCUCCUCCUCUCCUCGAGAUGCUCCUCGUCUCCACCGGCUGCUCCUCGUCUCCGCCGGCUGCUCCUCGUCUCCGCCGGCUGCUCCUCGUCUCCGCCGGAUGCUCCUCCUCUCUGCCAGACACUACUCCUCGUCUCUGCCAGACACUACUCCUCCUCUCCGCCAGACACUACUCCUCGUCUCUGCCAGACACUACUCCUUGUCUCUGCCAGACACUACUCCUCGUCUCCGCCAGACACUACUCCUCGUCUCUGCCAGAUGCUCCUCCGCUCCACGAGAUGCUCCUCCUCUCCACGAGAUGCUCCUCCUCUCCACGAGAUGCUCCUCGUCUCCGCCAGAUGCUCCUCCGCUCCACGAGAUGCUCCUCGUCUCCGCCAGAUGCUCCUCCGCUCCUCGAGAUGCUCCUCCUCUCCACCGGAUGCUCCUCAUCUCCGCCGGAUGCUCCUCGUCACCGCCGGAUGCUCCUCGUCUCCGCCGGAUGCUCCUCCUCUCCGCCGGAUGCUCCUCCUCUCCACCAGAUACUACUCCUCCUCUCCACCAGAUACUACUCCUCUCUGCCAGAUACUACUCCUCUCCGCCAGAUACUACUCCUCCUCUCCGCCAGAUGCUCCUCGUCUCCGCCAGAUGCUCCUCGUCUCCACGGGAUGCUCCUCGUCUCCACGGGAUGCUCCUCCUCUCCACCAGAUGCUCCUCCUCUCCUCGAGAUGCUCCUCAUCUCCACCGGAUGCUCCUCGUCUCCACCAGCUGCUGCUCCUCUCCACCAGCUGCUCCUCAUCCCCACUGGAUGCUCCUCAUCCCCGCCGGAUGCUCCUCCUCUCCGCCAGAUCCUACUCCUCCUCUCCGCCAGAUCCUACUCCUCCUCUCUGCCAGAUCCUCCUCCUCGUCUCCGCCAGAUCCUCCUCCUCGUCUCCGCCAGAUCCUCCUCCUCGUCUCCGCCAGAUGCUCCUCCUCGUCUCCGCCAGAUGCUCCUCGUCUCUGCCAGAUGCUCCUCCUCCCCACGAGAUGCUCCUCAUCUCCACCGGAUGCUCCUCAUCUCCACCGGAUGCUCCUCGUCUCCACCAGCUGCUCCUCGUCUCCACCAGCUGGAGGACUCCAGCCCCUUCCUGCCCUGGCCUCUUGCUCAGUGGCUUGUUGGGUGGGGACAGAGGCCCCUGGGGCACAGCAGGGGAGGCUCAGCCCUUUGUGGGCCUCGUGUGAGCUGCAGCUCCUGGAAGCACCCCCACCAGGCAGGAGUGAGAGGUGCAGGGCAGGGAUGGAGCAUCUGCUGUGUCACCAAAGUCCCUGCAGGAGCCAGGAGCACGGUGGACGCAGCUGAGCCCCGGCUGUGACUGCGAGAGCAACAGAGACUGUGGUGCUGGCACUAGGAUCUGUCCCUGGAGGGAAGCCACAUGCUCCCCACUCAGAGGAGGAGAGGGAGUCUUCCUAGGGGUGUGGGGGGCUCCAGGACAUGCCUGUAAGACGAGUUUCACCAGAAUCCACCCAGAGCCCUCUCGUUCAGACACGCACACGUGCAUAUUCAUAUGUACACAGCACAUACAUGCUCGUACAUACCACACAUGUGCACAGGAGGGCACGGGCAGGUGACCUGCAGCAUCUCUGAUCCGGGUGUCUCUAAGGCAGUCAGAGGCCACAGGCGGAGAUGCUGUGUGCACUGUCUAUUCCCGUGGAGACACAUGGGGGCCGUCCCUGUGGUGCACAUGAUAAUGCAGAGGCUCCCAGAGGGUGAGCUCUGCCCAUCACUCAGCCAGGGAGGGAGGGGCCCUUUUCAGGGAGCCGCAUGCCACGCAGAGCUUGUCCCACUGGGUAGUUUCCUCUGAUCAAAGUGGGGCACCAUCCAGGCUGCAGAGAGAAAGGGGACCCCCCAAAGCCAGCACCCACCCUUGACUGAAAGACACCACAGAAGAUAAGUGCCCAUCGGCCCCAGAGUCAUCAUUUCCCAGACAACCGGAAAUGGGCCCUGGACGGGCUGUCCUGGACAGGCUGCCGGGCAGUUGGGUGUGACUCAGUUGCGGCCUCCAACUGUGCCAACCAGAAAGGCACCCAGAGAAGCUUCCGGAAAUACGGUUGGUUUGUCCCCUUGGUGGGGCAGGAGGCGGCAGCUCUGCCGGGUGGCUCCCAGCACCCUCCCCCACAGAGCAAACAUCGGCAUGAGUCUGUCCACCCGUGUAUUCGUCCUGUCGCCGCGUGUGGCUGGCCUCAUUCUGGGUAUGCUGGCGGCAGCCACCUCUAGGACAGGGAGGUCCCAUGGCUCUGCAGACACAGGAGCUUGGCAGUGGCUUAGCUGUUAGAAUGUGAGCCUUCCAGAGUCAGACGCGCCUUUGCCUUCUGUUGGGCUCUGAGCUCAUUUCCUCAAACCCAGGAUGGUGCCAUAUACGGAGAGAGGCAUAGGUUGUCUUACGAGAGUGGGGUCGCGUUGCACUGUGGCCCCUGCCAGGCCCUGUCCGGAGUGCUGAACACAGAGCAGCAGGUGCCGCCGGUCCCCAGCCUCUUGGAGCCCCGUUCCCUCUGGGCGUCGUAGACAGUCGAGUUCAGCACAUCUCUACGUGGAGUUUCGCAAAAAAGGCAACCACUUUGAAAUGGGAGGGCCGCAGCGCCAUGGCCUGGCGACGCCUGUGAGUGACUACAGUGGGGCCUGGAGGAGGAGCAGGGGGAUGAAUGCAGCCUUGGGGCAGGCGCUGGGGCCUGGAGGAGGCUUGGGGAGCAGGGCAUGGGGGGCGGGGAGCGAGUGCAGCCUUGGGGCAGGCGCUGGGGCCUGGGCCUGGCUGGGCCCCUCUAUGCCUUUCAGUCUUGAGGUCUGGAAACCCGGCCGGGAUCUCCCCCGAGUGGGCAGUGCUGUUGGUGGCGGCGGGGGGGAGUGGUGCUGGCACUGUGUGGCCGGGCAGAGCCGAGGCCAAAGCAGUUCCAUCCACACGCAGUCCACGAAGGGACGUCGGGCGCCUCCCACAAGCAAAGGCCCCGCCCGGCUCCAGCCCGGCCCGCAGGGACGACCUUGCCCUUCUUUCCUCCCUGGCCAACAGCACCACCCCGUGGGGGCCCCGGUGCUGAGGGCUCAGGCUGCCUGUUUCCGUCCUGGAAACCACAGACACCCGAGAUCCAAGCAAGGAAGGCAGGAUUUCCAUACCUCCUCCCCAGCUGAGCAUUCGCUGGAGGGGGACGGGGCUGUCACUACGUCCCUUAUGAUGAUCACCUCAUAGAGGCUGGGCCUCCCCACACCAGGACCACACGCCCAUGAGGGCCCCACAGGCCUCAGCCUAGAGAGCCCCCAUGGGAAACCCUGUGCUGUGAAUGGUGUGGAAAUUCCCCUGUGUCCUUCCCACGUGACCCCACAAAACCCUCAGCCGUGGACAUCCCGAGUUCCUCUGAACGCCCGGCCUUCCCAAGCCUCGCCAGCGCCACGGACAUCCCGGGGCCCCGGGGAAGGGUGGCUCUGCCGGGAGACAGGGUCUUCUCUCUGGCUCUGGUUCUGAAGGCUGUGGUGGGUGCAAGGUUCACCAGAGACGGCAGGACUCCCGUGCCCUGGAGCGGGAGGGAGUCUCUCCUGUGUCUCCCCUGGGCGCCGGCUCCUGCUGAACCCCAGACCCAGCUGUGGGAGAAAGCUGCCCAGGGCCCUGCAGGAGAGGCGGGGCCAGCCCUGGUGCACACAGGGGCAGAGGCACCUGGGCUGGUCUGGGCUGGGAGGUCAACUCUCCGUGUUGCAAUGCUGUGUCCAGGUCUGAAAAGGGCAAUGUGAAAGCAACUCCUCAGGGACAGAAGCCAGGCCACUCUGGGGAGAGGCAGGACACAGCCCUUCUGGCCCUGAACACCUUGAGGGGCAGGCAGGGGGUGAUGACCCCACUCUACAGAUGGGAGCACCGAGGUGCCCAAGGCAGGGGGUGAGGACCCCACUCUACAGAUGGGAGCAGUGAGGUCCCCAAGGUGGGGGUGAUGACCAUAUUCUCCAGAUGGGAGCACCGAGGUCUCUGAGGCAGGGGGUGAUGACCCCACUCUACAGAUGGGUGCAUUGAGGUCCCUCAGGCAAGAGUGAUGACCCCACUCUACAGAUGGGAGCACCGAGGUGCCCGAGGCAGGGGGCGAGGACCCCACUCUACAGAUGGGAGCACCGAGGUUCCCAAGGCAGGGGGUGAGGACCCCACUCUACAGAUGGGAGCAGUGAGGUCCCCAAGGUGGGGGUGAUGACCAUAUUCUCCAGAUGGGAGCACCGAGGUCUCUGAGGCAGGGGGUGAUGACCCCACUCUACAGAUGGGUGCAUUGAGGUCCCUCAGGCAAGAGUGAUGACCCCACUCUACAGAUGGGAGCACCGAGGUGCCCGAGGCAGGGGGCGAGGACCCCACUCUACAGAUGGAAGCACUGAGGUCCCCGAGGUGGGGGUGAUGACCGUAUUCUCCAGAUGGGAGCACUGAGGUCUUUGAGGCAGGGAGUGAGGACCCCACUCUACAGAUGGUUGCACUGAGGUCCCUCAAGCAAGAAUGAUGACCCCACUCUACAGAUGGGAGCACCAAGGUCCCCAAGGCAGGGGGCGAUGGGAGCACCAAGGUGCCUGAGACAUGAGUGAUGACCCCACUCCACAGAUGGGAGCACCGAGGUCCCUCUGUGGGCAGCUUGGGGCCAGGCACAGGACUGGCAGAGGCUGGGAGCACAGCUUGUCGGGGCAUCUGCGGGUGUGAGGGCCUGACACUGUCUUCAGGGCUUAGCCUUUGUUCUCCCUGCAAGAGGGGACAGAAUGCCCUUUGUCUUUGUAAAUCUAUGCCCUGCUUUAGGCAAAAAGAGGAAUCCGGAGAGCACUCCUGGACCUGUUUCUUCUUAAUCGUCUUCAUCUCAAAGGCCCUUCCUGUUUUGGGGAGUCACACACACUCUUCUGACACUGACGACCUGGAGUGUCACAGACCCUGAAGGUGAAGGGCUCUGUCCCACAAGACUCUGCCCCUACUUCUGAUGACAGCCGUACAUGGGUACCCAGGCAACCCACACUCACUCCUGACAACUGCAGAUUUGGGGAACUUUACAUCCCCUCAGAUUCACUAGAACACCUCCCAGGGCUCAGGAAAGUGCUUUACGUACAAUCAUGCUUAUUAUGAAGGAAACCCAUGAACAGCUCAGUGAAGAGAGUGGGGAGGUGGGCACUGAUCUCUGAGCACCGUGGGGGCUCCCCAGCCUGGGGGCUCCCCAACCCUGAUGCCCAAAAGUUUUUAUCUAGGCCUCAUUACACAGGUAUGAUUGAUUAAGUCAUUGGUCAUUGGUGAUUGAACACAAACUCAAUCUCUGGCCCCUCCCAGGAGUGGGGGCGGUGAGGGGGGCUGGAAGUUCCUCUCUAAUUACAUGGUUGGUUCCUCUGGCAACAAGCUCCCACCCUAAAGCUACCUUGGGGUCCCCCAAGAGUCACCUCAUUAGGGUAAACAAAUGUGGUGAAAAAGAGUUGUUAUGAAAUCAGACACCCCUAUCAGGAAAUUCCAAAGAUUUAAGGAGUUCUGUCCCUGGAACAGGGGACAAAGACCAGAUGUAUUUUUUAUUAUACCACAAUACAAAUCUCUUAAUUUAUUCAGGUCUCCUUCGAUUUAUCUCAGUAGCGUUUUGUAGUUUUAGGUGAUAAGCUCAUGCACACUGAGAUUCAAAGGGGUCUGUUGGAGCGUUCAGCAAUUCAUGAACUGAGCAGUACCAGAACGUGUGAGGUUCAGCGUGAGGUUCAGCGCUCCACUGAGGUUGAGGGGCGGAGCUCUUUUCUAAGUGUCUGCAGAAGCGGGACAAAGACAAGACAUCUGGUUAAAAGGAAGUCCCUGGUGAGAGGCUGGUUUGGCAGUUUCUGGGCAGUGUCAGUUUCGUGGCCCAGUUCCCAGUGGGCUUCGGUGUGCUCACACAGGGUCCCAGGCACUGAAGCCGCCUCAGCCCAGGGCCUCCUGGUUAACUUUCUCAUGUAGCUUUCCGAGUAUAUGUCCACCACUUGUUUUGGUCAAAGCCACUCAUAAGUAAUUUAACAUUUUUGAUGUCAAGAACAAUAAAUAGAAGUUUCCUCUUUGUGCCUCCCCAGUCACUGGGCUUCAGUCCCAGGAGGCAGGUGCCAGGCAGACGUUGGUCCCUUCUGCUAGUUUUGCCUGGUCUUGAACCGGUGCUGUGGGCUCUUCUGGGGCUGGUUCCUUUCAUGCUGAGUCAUGUCUAUGUGACUCCUCAGUAGUUAGUUUUUUAAAAAAUUGCCAGAUAUAAAUGUGUGCUCAGGCAGGUUUUUGAGAACUCCACACCAUCUCUUGGGAACGAUGAGAAGUCCCCUGAGUCCCUGUGGCAGGACGUGGGCUUUUCAUGGGUCAGCCUGAGCCCCGCUCCAUGGCCCCGAUGGGCGCUGGGGCAGCACCCUGGCUGGACAUGGGCUCCUAGAGAGGGCAGUCAGUGCUCGGCAGGCCAGAAUCAUGGAGGAGGGGUCGGGAAAGCACUGCUGACCCCCAAUCCCAUGGAUAUGCUGUCAUCCUCCCAAUGGCCUGGCUGAUGGGCCAUGGUGGGUGUGGACCCCUGAGUGAGUGUCUGGGGGGAAGUGUCACGGGGUCAGCCUGUGUGCUUCCUGGGCUCCUUGUCUACAUGGCUGCGCAUCUGCUUGGCUGUGUGUCCGGGACCUGCUUGUGUCCACUACAGGCCUGGGCCCAAGGAAUCUCGGGAGGUGGAAAUGGACACCCGGGGCCGCAGAAGCUGCACAGGUGGGGCCAAGAACCAACCAAGCCUUGCUGCCAGCUCCCCGCUCCACCCACUGUGAUGCCAGCUGCUUCUCACAUCUGUGAAGCCUCACCCAGCCUUGGGCCAUCAUUUCAGGUAAAUAAAAAGGCCUAAUGGCCCCAUCAGGCCCUGAGCUCCCUGCUUCCUGAGGAGCUGUCUUCUGCUGGAACUUGGAGGCCACGUGGGCAGAAUGAAACUCCUGCUUCCGACAGCAGACGGCAGCAGUGACCUACUCCUGGCUGCCCUGCCCAUCUGGAGCGGGUUCUGGGUCUUUUGGGCCCUUUGAGGUUGGUCCGCCCUCCUGCCCUGGCAGCAGCCAGUAUUUUACUCCCAGUUGCUCCAGCCUCCCCCAACCCCCUUCCCCGUAAGUAACCUGCCCCGACGCUUGUCCUGGAGCCACGGUGUGGAAGAUUCCAGCAGCAUUGAGGAACCAAAUUUUAUAUACAGCGUUUCCUCCAAGCACGCAGCUCUGAUGUGCCUUUUCCAGGGCCAAAGGCCCCUUCAGGAAUCUUCAGGCUUCCCGCUCCACCUCACCUUCUGUAGUGCUGCCAGGCUGACGACAGCCCCCGGGUCUGUGGCUGGCCCCUCUCUCCCAGAGCAUCUUGGCCUGCAGUGCUGGCCACAGCCAGAGAGAGGGAAGAGACAGCCCCAGCAGUAACCACGGGUGCCUUCGGCCCACGCACCUGCCGGUCGGCCCCAAGGGUGCCAGGCCUUCCUCUCCUAUCGCCGCUGUGGGGCUCCAAAGGGCAGCCAGGAGCCCCAGCUCUGCUGUGGCUUUGCUGUUCCCCAACUGUGAGACCCUCAGAGAGCUGCCGGGCGCAGGUUUCCUCCUCGGCCAGCGAGCAGUCAGACCAGGCUUCGGACCCCUCUACUGUUCCAGGGUGGAGGGGAGGACCCAGGAGACCCAAUGGCCUGGAUGCCAACAGCCAGCGUGGCCUGACGAUGCCAUAGGGCACAGGGACAGGCUCUCCGUCCUCUGCGGCCCCGUUCUGCUCCCACCCCAGUGCCCUCCUUUCACCCUGGGGUCCUCCCUGGACCAGCAGCUGCCACCCACAGCACACUGGGAUAUUUGUGCUGGCCUAGCUACUACCUGACACAGCUGACCACCUCACCCGGCUGACGACCCACACAGCCUCCUGGCCUGGGUCCUCCUGCGCCAGCAUUGUGUGUCAAGUGUGUGUGUGGCUGGCAUUCCUGUGUGCCGCGUGCAGAGCCUGCAGGACGCCCUUCAGUUCCCAGGAUGCCCCACCACAGAGGGGGACUGGUCCCCCCGAGGGUCCUGGGAAACCCUGUUCCAACCACAUGCCACAUAGGUCCUGUUACGUGAGUUAGAGGGGUGCGUGUGCUUCUCAAGAUGAGCUUUCAUCAAGUUCUUCCUCCACGCGACGUUGGUCCAAUUGGCCGGUGGGGAGUACAGUGCUAGGUGAGGGUCUCCGCUGGGGAGCUUGACACAGCGGGGCGCAAAUAAAGCCGUCACCAAUCCAAACCCGUUCUGCACUGAUACCUCGUACAAUAGCAAUAAAAAUGUGUCAGCAAGAACGCCAAAUUCGGUUAGCGUUUUAAACGCGGCAUUCACUCACGGUGAACGGGCAGCGGUGGGUUUACUGCCCUGCACUCCAGCCCACAGUGCGGUGAACUGGACCCUAAAUCACAGUGAACGGGCGGCGGUGGGUUUACUGCCCUGCACUCCAGCCCACAGAGCACUGGACUCUAAACAUGCACUGACCUCAAGGUGGUUCCCCUGGCUGACCUCCUGUCACAUGGCCUGGAUAAGACUGGCAAUGGCCAGAUCUUGUCACAAUCUGAACAAAAGGGUCAAUAUGUAGAGAAACAGACUGACGAUUCGACGCCUCCCAAGGGAGGAACAAAAUGAGCUACAUUUUCGUUUACUAGAGCACAGUAUUAAGGGCCUUGACUUGGGAGUAGCUCAGAUGAAGACUUGGUUUGUUUUUCUUUCCUUUCUUUCUUUCUUUCUUUCUUUCUUUCUUUCUUUCUUUCUUUCUUUCUUUCUUUCUUUCUUUCUUCUUUCUUUCUUUCUCUCUCUCUCUCUCUCUUUCUUUCUUUCUUUCUUUCUUUCUUUCUUUCUUUCUCAGAUUCUCGCUCUGUCGCCCAGGCUGAGUGCAGUGGCGCAGUCUCGGCUCACUGCAAUCUCUGCCUCCAGGGUUCACGCCAUUCUCCUGCCUCAGCCUCCUGAGUAGCUGGGACUGCAGGGGCCCACCAUCACACCUGACUAGUUUUUUGUAUUUUUAGUAGAGAUGGGGUUUCUCCAUGUUAGCCAGGAUGGUCUCUAUCUCCUGACCUCGUGAUCCGCCUGUCUUGGCCUCUUAAAGUGCUGGGAGAAGACCUGAUGGUUUCAGUGGACCACAAGCCAUGUGGUGUGGCCUGGGAGAGGGCACAAAGUAACCUGCCUGCUGUUCCCGGGAAGAUGCCUCAUCACACAUCCGAGGGCCCAUGAAACCCGGAACGGCCCACGCACAACUGGAGAGCCUGACACACACCUGGAGGGUCCUUCGCACACCUGCAGAGCCCGUCACACACCUGGAGGGCCCGUCACACACCUGGAGGACUCAUCACACACCUGGAGGACUUGUCACACCUGGAGGAUCCAUCACACACCUGGAGGACUUGUCACACACCUGGAGGGCCCAUCACACACCUGGAGGACUUGUCACACACCUGGAGGGCCCAUCACACACCUGGAGGACUUGUCACACACCUGGAGGGCCCAUCACACACCUGGAGGACUUGUCACACCUGGAGGAUCCAUCACACACCUGGAGGACUUGUCACACACCUGGAGGGCCCAUCACACACCUGGAGGACUUGUCACACACCUGGAGGGCCCAUCACACACCUGGAGGACUUGUCACACACCUGGAGGGCCCAUCACACACCUGGAGGACUUGUCACACACCUGGAGGGCCCAUCACACACCUGGAGGACUUGUCACACCUGGAGGAUCCAUCACACACCUGGAGGACUUGUCACACACCUGGAGGGCCCAUCACACACCUGGAGGACUUGUCACACACCUGCAGAGCCCGUCACACACCUGGAGGGUCCAGCACACACCUGCAGGACUCAUCACACACCUGGAGGGCCCGUCACACACCUGGAGGGCCCAUCACACACCUACAGGGCCGCAAGGGGAACAUUUCCAAGGCCAUUGUCAGUGCGGUGUAAGGAGGACCUUUCUCCCCAUCGGAGCAGGUAACCCAGCAAGGAAGCCCAUCCAGCAGCAACCUGCCCUGGCACCUGGUCCUGGCAGGCAGCAGGAUGGCCUCAGCAGAGCCGGGAUCAGAAUGGGGUGGCAGGGGGGUGCAAGCCCACUGGAGGGGGUCCCGGCAGUGAGGUGACCCUGGACAUGGGGAGCUGGGCAGCUUCUCUGCAUCCAUCUCCAGGUGACCUGGAGGGGUCUGGAGCAUCAGGGGAGGGGAAGGCAGCCUCCAGGACAAGAUGAGCCCUGCCACCUGAGGGGCUUGUGUCUGGAGAAGGUUUCCAGCAGGAGGGGAGCAAGGUCACAACCUGGGGAGGGAUCCAUCCCGGGGUGACUGGGGUCUGUGAGGCCUUGGGGUGACCUGCAGCGUGCGUCUUGGGAUGCACUUGUACCGCAUUCCUUCCUGUCGGGAUACUGAAGGUCCCGAGCCAGAGGAGAGGAGAGGCAGAGCAGCCCGUCAGUGAUGACCAAACCUGCCCACGAUGAGUGUGUGGAGGAGGCGCGCUCGUGGAGAUGUGCCAGCCGGGUGCAGGGACUGCGGGCAUUUGCUGAGAGCCUCCUCCACCAGGUGUUUCCAUGGAAUGUCUGGUAGGGCUCCCACCAGCCCUGGCCACAGGCCCUGCUGCCUUCCCUCACGUUGCAAGGGGCCAUGCCUGACACUCGUCAUCACCCACCAACAGAGCGUAAGCCAAAAAUAAAACACUAAGGUUCCCAACCAUCUGAGUGGACCUCGUCCUCACCAGAGCCCUCUUAAAAUGUAACCCGAGAGGUGGUUUCCAGCCAUGACGGGAACGGGGGUCAGACAUGCCUCGUUCUACCUUUCCAGCAUUAACGUCCACACAGACCUGAAGUCUGAUGAGAAACAUUUCACAGCCCUCUGAAGCUGCUACCUGAAGGCCUCCUCCACAAAUAAGAACCUGGGUUUCCAGGAUCCUGGAUCUGAACUCAGGCAUUCCUUUCUAUUAUUGAUCCCAGGUCUUUAGAUAAAUGUAACCAAUUGUCCACCGGAAAGUUUUUAAAUCUUCCUAUAACCUGAGAGUUCUGCUCCCCUGACUGCUUUGCAUUGCCCUGCCUUUCUGAGCCGAACCAGCAUAUUUCUUAAAUGUAUUGCCUGAAGUCUCAUUCUCCCUAAAAUGCAUAAAAGCAAGCUACUCUCUGACCACCCUGGACACAUGUCCUCAGGCCCUCCUGAGGGCUGGGUCAUGGCCCACGGUCACUUGUCUUGGGCUCAGAAUGAAUCUCCCCACAUUUUACAGAGUUUGACUCUUUGUUGACAGGAGCCAACGCUGCUGUCUGACCCCGGCCCGGAGCUCUCCCCGAGCUCUCCUGUGGGAGGCAGCCAUUUGCAGAAAUGGAGCCGAGCCUCAGUGGGACUGUCAGGGCCCAGGGACCCGAGGGGCCAGCGCUCCCUGAGGGCAGGGCUCAGCAUCCACCAAGCGGGCCUUAGAGAGCCAUGGCCGCCGGCCAUCUGCAGUGCUCGUGAGGGGCACUGACUGCUCCCACCUGGCUCCCACCUCACCUCCGGCGGGCACUGGGGCGCUGUGCCUUUCUCAGAGGCAUCAGGGAGUCCAAGGAGACGCCAGAGGACCUGUGUCCCAUCCUCAAGGUAAAGGGCACAGUAACUGGCUGACCGAUCACCAACAGGCCGCCUCCGCUGCCUGGAGCCCGCUGGCCCAGGGGUUCCUACCGCGCCCUGCCGUCUCCCUCAUCCUCCCUCACUGCAUCCAGACACCCAGUCCCCUGGUUGCCCGUGCCCGCGUCAGCUCUGGCCAUCCUUGUCCUGGGGGCUGGGCAUGGAUUUUGCUGUCUCGUGUUCUCAGGACUGUAUGAAGUCCAGCCCAUUUGGCAAGCAUCCUGUGGAGGUAAGGCUGUCUCUCAGUGGCUCCUGAGCUGAUGUGUCCAACUACAGGUCCAGGUGGUGUCUGCCGAGUCUCCUGGUCAAAUCGCCGUCCUUCCUCUGUAGGGGAUAAUCGUCCUGGAGACACUGGGAGACCAAAUCCUGAUUCUCCUGGAACUUCUCUGAUUUUGGCAUCCAUGGGGGUCUUGUCAGCAGCAAUCAGUUCCGUGGACUUUGACUCGUGGUGAUUUUCUGUUUCCCCAUUUCCUCAGGCAUUUAUCCAUCGAGGUUCUCCUGCAGGGAAGAGCAGUGGGUCCCUCCUCCCGGGCUGCGUGUUGACCCGGCCAGUGGCGACAGCAGCAGAACUCAUAUGCGUCUAUUGUAUUCUGUGGUUUGUGAAAAGUGUAGGUCAGUGACCACAGUAGUGGAUUCUGUGGUUUGCAAUCAGCACGGCCUCUGUGCGUUUUGUUGCUCAUGCCACCAUGAUCGGCCUUUGGCAGCUCUUCAUGUUGGCCCCUGUGACCUUCACAAGCUCUUACUUUUUAAUUAAUUAAAUCUGGGGGUGAGCCUCCGGCUCUGGGCUCCACAGGACUUCAGCUCAUUGCAAACUUCCCUGCUCUGGAGGAGCAAUGAGUCAGCCGCCGGCAAGGACAGCCCAUUUGGAGGUAAAGUGCUAAGGGGAGAGGAAGGCGGUGAGAGUAAAGCAGUGGCAGGAACUGCUCAGAGGACAGGUGACAUGCGGAGGCCUAGGGCAGACCUCGUCCAGGGCGCUGGGCAGGUCCAGGCAGGUCCUCCAGGCCAGGGACCCUGCGCAGCUGCCUUCUGGGUGGGGAGAGUGGGGGCAGCACCCAGGGUGCCUGGCGUGCUGUGCUGAAGGCCACCUGCGAGGCUGGAACUGUGUCUCCAUCUGACAGGCAGAGAAACAGCAGCAGCCCAGCCUGGGAAACGAUGUCAACAGCUCCUGUUUCCAGCACGUUCCUGGGUCUCAGACGCCCAGCCUCACACACAGAGUCCCAGAGACCAGGGUAUCGAAUGCCCAGCCUCACACAUGGAGUCCCAGAGGAGAUCAGGGUCUCGAACGCUCAGCCUCACACAUGGAGUCCCAGAGACCAGGAUCUCGAACGCUCAGCCUCACACAUGGAGUCCCAGAGACCAGGGUCUCGAACGCUCAGCCUCACACAUGGAGUCCCAGAGACCAGGGUCUCGAACGCUCAGCCUCACACACGGAGUCCCAGAGGAGACCAGGAUCUCGAACGCUCAGCCUCACACAUGGAGUCCCAGAGACCAGGGUCUCGAACGCUCAGCCUCACACAUGGAGUCCCAGAGACCAGGGUCUCGAACGCUCAGCCUCACACACGGAGUCCCAGAGGAGACCAGGAUCUCGAACGCUCAGCCUCACACAUGGAGUCCCAGAGACCAGGGUCUCGAACGCUCAGCCUCACACACGGAGUCCCAGAGGAGACCAGGAUCUCGAACGCUCAGCCUCACACAUGGAGUCCCAGAGACCAGGGUCUCGAACGCUCAGCCUCACACAUGGAGUCCCAGAGACCAGGGUCUCGAACGCUCAGCCUCACACACGGAGUCCCAGAGGAGACCAGGAUCUCGAACGCUCAGCCUCACACAUGGAGUCCCAGAGACCAGGGUCUCGAACGCUCAGCCUCACACAUGGAGUCCCAGAGACCAGGGUCUCGAACGCUCAGCCUCACACACGGAGUCCCAGAGGAGACCAGGAUCUCGAACGCUCAGCCUCACACAUGGAGUCCCAGAGACCAGGGUCUCGAACGCUCAGCCUCACACAUGGAGUCCCAGAGACCAGGGUCUCGAACGCUCAGCCUCACACACGGAGUCCCAGAGGAGACCAGGAUCUCGAACGCUCAGCCUCACACAUGGAGUCCCAGAGACCAGGGUCUCGAACGCUCAGCCUCACACACGGAGUCCCAGAGGAGACCAGGAUCUCGAACGCUCAGCCUCACACAUGGAGUCCCAGAGACCAGGGUCUCGAACGCUCAGCCUCACACAUGGAGUCCCAGAGACCAGGGUCUCGAACGCUCAGCCUCACACAUGGAGUCCCAGAGACCAGGGUCUCGAAUGCCCAGCCUCACACAUGGAGUCCUAGAGGAGACCAGGGUCCCAGACGCCCAUCCUCACGCAGAGCCCCAUAGGAAACCAGCACCUGCGUCUUCUGUCUGGGUGGCACAGGGAAAGUGCUUCCCCUGGGAAUACUCGGCUGGCAUCCACCCCGCCAGUGUGUGCUGCAGGCUGGCUCAUCUGGGGGUGGGGGGCUUGGCGGCAGCACCGCAGGGUCUAGGGGAGCCCACCUGGCUCUGGCCUCCUGCUCUUCGCUUCCGGGGAAACGGCCCAGGCCCCUGCUGCACACUCUUCCUUCCCCUCUUCAGUAGUAAGAGGAGCCAAAUGCGGCUGACGGUGCAUCUGAGGCCGAGGCGCAGCCCCCGCCCCUGGGGUGGACUUUGGCCGCAUGGGCAGGGCCAGGCAGGCAGGUAGCCUCUUGGGGCCUCUGAGGUGGCCCGAAUGCCUCCCCUGAUCACGGCUGCCACCCGGGCAUCCUGGUCCCCCUGCGUCAGAGCCCACACACAUGACAGACAGGAGGCUCUGGCUCAGAUGAGGCCAGCGGCACUUCCUUUCAUCCUGCCUGGCACCCGGUUUCUUGAUGACCCAGGCCAGUGUUUUUCACGCUGAAUCGUGUUUGACUUAGAAGCACAUGGGAUGAUCCCUUUGGCCUUCCCAGCACCUCCUGAGAAGUAUUGUCAUCAGACCUGUGAGCAUGAGAUGGCGCUGGGCCCAGAGAGGUCAGUGCCCUGGCCCAGGAUACACAGCGCACAGGAGGUCACUGGGAGCCUGAGUGACAACAUCUCCAGGGCUGGACAGCCUCCCUGUCAGGGGUGAGAAACGGGUCUGUGCCCAUUUCACGGCUAAGAACCUGGAGCAGGUCCCCCUUCAGCCCAAAGCCCAGGAGGAGGCGGCUGCUUAUUGCAAAAGGUGUGAACCAGGCUGAGUGGUGCCGCCCUCCCCAUCCACGUGGUCCCCAUCUUUCCCAUCCACGUGGUCUCUGUCCUCCCCAUCAACGUGGUCCCCGUUCCCCCCGUCCAGGUGGCCCCCAUCUUCCCAGUUGGGUGAUCCCCGUGUUCCCCGUUGGGUGGUCUGCGUCCUCCCCAUCGGGUGGUCUCUGUCCUCCCCAUCGGGUGGUCUGCAUCCUCCCCAUCGGGUGGUCUCUGUCCUCCCCAUCGGGUGGUCCCCUUCUGGCUCUGGGUUGCCUGCAUCUUGCAGCUCCACACUCCGGAACAUGUGGCUUCUGGCAUCACCGGGGCGGGGGGAAGGGGCCAGCUGCAGCCCUUGGCUGGAACGUGUCAGGCAGCCAAGCCUAUGUGCAAAGGGCCGGGACCUGAAGGAGUGAGAAGCCGGACGCUGUUGUCCCUGACCCUGAGCUGAGCAAGUUCCACUGAGGCCACAGAGAUGAGUCCGACCUGAAUUCUGCCCUCCCGGAGUUUACAACAGGGUGAAAGGCACCUGGCGGGUCUGGAAUGCCAGCUUGGAAGGGAUCGUGGGAGGAGCUGGCUGAGGAAACGUGGGCCUGGGGUGGGGGUGGCUGGGUUCCCAGGGAGGCCGCAGGUGCUGUGGUGUGCACAGCAGGGCCUGAGCCUCCUGGGGCCAGGAGGCUUCCUGGGCGUGAGGCCCAAGCUGAGUUUUCCAUAGGGAUUGAGAGUGAGUGAAGGCUGUUUGGAAGGACGUGCUGGGCAGUGGGAAGUUUGAGCAAAACCUGGAGACAGGAAAGAGCUGUGUGUUGAGAGAAGCUACAGCUGGUGCAGUGUUUCUGGAAUGGAAAGUUCACGGCGGACGUGUGGAAGGGAGCGACUCCCAGUGGUGGGCACAGCAAGGGCCCCUCCCAAAGACGUCGGAGGCUGAACCCCCAGGACGCUUGAACAGGGCAACCUUGCAGGGGGAACUAGGUUAGGAAUCCCAAGUCGGGAGAUAGCCUUGGAUUAUUCGGUGGGUGCUCCUGGAGUUUAGGGAGGAUGGAGAGGCUGCUGGACCCAGCGUAAGGUCUGGGCUCCUUAGAGGCAGGUGGGCGGGUCAAAGAGAGAGCAAUUUGAAGAUGCUGGGUUUGAAGAUGGGCCGUGGGCCAAGGCUGCUGCCGUCUCUGGAGGCUGAGAAAAGAAAGCAGUGGCUUCUCCACCAGGCUCCUGCCAGCCCUGCCUUCAGCACCCUGAGGCCCUUUUCACACUUUCCCCUCCAGGACUGUAAGAUAAUACAUUUGAGCUGUUGGAAGCCACUAGGUUUGUGGUAAUCUGUUAAAGCAGCAGAUAGGAACCUCAUAGACUCACUAUUGAGAAAAGAAAAGCACUUUUAUCUGAGGAGCAAGUCCUUUUAAUUAUUGGGUCCAGAGAGGCGUUCAGUUGAGGCCGCAACCACAUCCCACUCCCCCUUUGAGCUGCAUGUUCAUCUUGUGAAAGGAAAAUCAUUCUCGGGACCCCAGAUCGCUGAGCCUAAGAGAAAAGUCCAGCUGGGAACUGUGCCAGGCAAACCUGCCUCCCAUUCUAUUCCUGAGUAAGGGAACUACAAAGAUUUUAAAAAGCUACACGCCUGCCUCACGAUUUGCCCACAAAGAAAUUCCUUGUGGACAAAGCACAGACAGAACUCAAAGUCACCCCACUGCUCCCGUGAGACAAACGCACACAGCUGAUCACUUCCUCUGCCCUCAUUUCACUGAGCCAGACUCAGGCAUGAGUGACCAUUCCUGUAAAUUGUGCAUUCCGUAAAAGGCUAAUCAGAAACUCAGGAGUGCAACCGUUUGUCUCUUAUCUACCUACGACCUGGAAGCCUCCUCCCUGCUUCCAUCUGUCCCGCCUUUCCGGACCGAACCAGCGUUCAUCCGAUGUAUGUUGAUGUCUCAUGUCUCCCUAAAAUAUGUAAAACCAAACUCUGCGCCGACCACCUCAGGCAUGUUGUCAGGACCUCCGGAGGCUGUGUCACAGGUGCGUCCUGAACUUUGGCAAAAUAAACUUCCUAAAUUGACUGAGCCUUAUCUCAGACGCCUUUUGGUUUACAACGCUACUGAGAUGUUCAUCUCACCUGCAGCUGUGUAUGAGAAGAGGUCGUGGCUGCAUCUGGAUUCGGAAAGACCCCAGUGCUAAUGAUUGUUACCAUAACCAAGGGAAAGGACUCUAACCUGUGCGGGUUUACGGCUGCCUUCUCGGCAAGCUUGAGAUUGUAGGAGCCAUACGUGGCCACGAUGUGGACUGCACUCUGGCUGGUGGCUGUGGCGUGACCACGGUCACUGCACAGUCACUUGGAUCCCUGGGAGGAGAGUCCUGUAGCCUCGGACCGGGGAUGCCACAGGCAUGAACCCACCUUUGCAAAAAUUAUAACAGUGGAAAAAUUAUGGCAGUGAAAGAGACCCGAGGUAACCAACUCCCAUCUUGCCUUUAGCCUUCAAACUGCCCUUAAUUAUUCCUGGGCUUGGGCCAAGCUAACUCUGGGAGACAUUUAGUUUAUAGCUUAAAUGAUAAUAACCCUUCCGCAAAACUCAACAGCCUUUGUAAAGCUAUUGAGAGACCACUAGGCUACGAGGACGAGAGGAGCCUGAAUUCUGCUAAAAUGGAGACACAAAGGAUUACCCCCCUUUAUUCUGGAGCUCAAAAUAUGCAACUUCCCAACUACUCCCGCAGAUAACGUCACUACGGUGGAACCUAAGACUGGCCUUUGAGAUGUCUUUUCAGGUUUUUUGCAAGUCUGACAACUGAUUUCCCCCCCUGGACCGGUCAGCCUCCCUGGUGCCACCCAGAAGCGACUCGGGGCACAAGGACCAUUUCCCACACCCCGACGACUGCACCCCCAACCAGUCAGCAGCAAGCGCCCUUGCCUACCCACCCGACUCUCUUCCCCUAAACUAGCCUUGAGAGACCCUGGUCUCUGCAUUUUCAGGGAGGCUGAUGUGAGUAACAAUAAAACUCUAGUGUCCUGUUUAGCCGGCUCUGCGUGUGUAAAACUGUUUCUCUAUUGCAGCUCUCGCCACUGGCCAGGAAACGGUUUCCCCCUCCUCGGGCUGUGCUGGGAGGAAGGGUCUGAAGUGGCUUGUAAUGUCGGAAGCAAAGUGGAGGACUUGCCCGGAAGAGGGAGGAAGGCCUUGGCUCCUUUGAGCCAGUGGGAAUGGAAGGGAAGGCGGCCAGGAUUUCCUCAAAAAUAUUUCCCCAUAGCCGGUCAGCUCCCCACGGGGCCAAUACCGCAUCCUCACUCUGGGCGCAAGGACGGCCCCUUCCCAGAGCCCAUUUAGAACUUGGAUGAAUGUUCUAUCAACACUCAUGGAUGUUGCCUGGAUGAAUGGGCUCUAUCCGGGCCUUGAGUAGGAAGAAGCCGCUGGCAGUUACUUGCUCACCCAGAGACUCCAAGCAGCCACACUCACCUGGGCUGAUGACUCAAUUGACUCCUGAGUUUCUCCGGCUCUUCAUUGAGGUCUGUCUUUUCCACCUCCAUCUUUGAGCCUCUGAACUUGAUGAAAAUCGGUUACAUGUAGAUGGCUUUUCUGUCCAAUGCUAGAGAACUUUGAACUUAAUGGAAUCCUGCCGUCUUUUCAUCAACUCAGUGCUAAACAACUCUAGAUUUUAAAAUGAUAUCCAGUGUGACUGCGUCCAUUUCACAUGGCACAAGGAUUGUCUGUGAUCACGAUUCAUAAAGCUGCUAUUUUUUAGCUGACACUAGGCCCAAGCAUGGCCCCUGGGGGCACAGGGCUGUUUAUUUCUCUUUUAAAGCACCCUAAUCUGGGAGGUGUAUUUUGCCGGUGGCUGGCGGGCUGGGAGCAGAGAAAAGUUCAGUGUAAAAAUGAAAAUGCAUUCCCGGCAGGAAAACUCCCACCCUAAGGGCACGUAUGCAGUUUACCCCAAAACAAUGGUUGCCGUGGGUAACCCGAGUGGUGUUGCCAGUGGCUGCCAGUUUGGCCCUUCCAGGGAGAUGUCAAGAGACCCCUUCUACCAAUCCCUUUCCUCAUUAAAGAGGAAGAAUGUUUGCUUUCUGGGAGAUAUUUAAGAGGACAAUUUGAAAUCCCACAAAAGCCAGGGUUGGUAGAAUCAGGACUUGGCUCAGCCCAGCUCAGCCCCGCAGCAGCUACCCCGGGCUCUGUUUGUCCUGGCUUCCACCAGGGCCAGCGCUUCACAGCCGGAAGCAAACAGGCCAAGCAUUUCUUGGUUAAUAGCACAAGGGGGCCAGGCUUGCUGGAGAAGCAGCGGUCAGGGCCAGGGGCCCCUAACCUCUGCAGUCGCCCCUCCCAGUGGCUUUCCAGAGCUGUUUUCCACCUCUCCCUGAGGAGCUGAAGGGCGCCGGGGGCCGAGUCACUGCCACAGCCGCAGGGACCAAGCCCCAUCCCAGCAAGGCUGAGGCCUCAGGAAGGCGGCCAGCCCAGGCCCUCUCGCCACUGGCCAGGAAACUGUUCCCCCCCUCGGGCUGUGCUGGGAGGAAGGGUCUGAAGUGGCUUGUAACGUCGGAAGCAAAAUGGAGAACUUGCCCAGAAGAGGGAGGAAUGCCUUGGCUCCUUUGAGCCAGUGGGAAUGGAAGGGAAGAAGGCCAGGAUUUCCUCAAAAAUAUUUCCCUGUAGCCAGUCAGCUCCCCACAGGGCCAAUACCUCGUCCUCACUCCGGGUGCAAGGACAGCCCCUUCCCAGAGCCCGUUUAGAACUUGCUUCUCUUCAGACUACAUUCCCUCCUGGCUGGAUUCUGGAGACCAUAACUGGGGCACCUACCAAGUGGGGCCCGUUAGAGGUGCUGGCGGAGUUCCCGUGUGACCCCAUCAGGGUGGCUCACAGCACAUCUCCGCAGCGACACGCUCAGGUCUGGUUUUCCAGUGUGUAUGCGUGGAGCCCAGCAGUGGGGCCCAGAUGGCGUGGUGAGGAUCACCACUGAAAGGCAGGCCUCGAGCACUUGCCCAGAGUCCACUGUUUGGAGGGCAGUUCGAUUCACCGUAGCCAAUUAGCCCACAGCACACACAAUCUUUCUUUUCCCAUUGAGUUGUCUUGGCACCUUGGUUGGAAAGUAAUUUACCAUGUAUGUGUGGGUCUAUUUCCUUUAUUUGAAAGUGAUUUUUAAAAGGAAAAUUGCAAGACCCCUUCUUCUAAUUGUGGCCCCACACCCUUGCCCAUGCAUCCGACUCAUCUCCAUCCAUCCUGUGUGUCUGGUAGUUUCAUAAAAAGUCAAACACAUACCUGCCAUUAUGACCCAGCGAUUGUACUCCUGGGCAUUUAUCGCAGAGAAAUUAAAAUGUAUAGUCACACAAACGAUCAUAGCAGCUUUAUUUGGAACAGCGAAAACCUGGGAACAGCCCCAUUGUCUGUCAGCAGGUGCGUGUCCGACGCAUCGUGGUGCCUCCACACCACACAACGUGCUCAGCAACGGAGAGAAACAGACUCUGGGAGAAAACUCCAUCUCAAAGGCUGCAUUCCGCACUCCGUUCCCAUAACACUCUUGAAAGGAUGAGUGACGCCGGCGGGUGCUGUGGGUUAGAGAAGGGCCCCGCGGGGCACACCUCACACCUGUGGGGAUGGACGGUCAUGCAUCUCGAAUGUGGUUGUGGUUACAGAAAUCCACAUAUGCGGCCACACAUCGCAGAAUCUCCACACGGAGUCGUACCCAGAAUAAAACAAACACACGGAAACCUAGGAUGUCCAAAUGAGCUCCGUCAUCCAGUGACUUGCGUGGUGCCCAUAUCAGUUUCCUGGUUUUAAGAAUUUGUUGUAGCUCUGCAAAGUGCUGCAUUGUAGGAAGCUGAGGAAUGGAAUGUGGGACCCCUCUGUACUAUUCGGCAACUUUUUGUGAAGCUAUAAUUAGCUCAAAAUGCAAAGCUAAAAUUACUGAGGACUUAGAAAUAAACUUGACAAAAGAUUUACAAGUCCUAUAUACUGAGAACUGAGAAACAUCAAUGAGAGGAAUGAAAAAAGGCCUAAAUAAAUGGAGCCAUAGCAUGUUCAUGGAAGAUGCCAACUCUCCCCAGAUUGAUCUCCAGAAUCAACACAAUCCCAAUCAGAAUCCCAGCAGGAUUUUUGUAGAAAUUGGUAAGCUAAUUCUAAGGUUUAUACAGAAAUGCACAGGACUUGGAGUAACCAAAGCAAGCAUAAAAAAGAACAGAGUUGAAGAAUUUAUAUUACUUGAUUUUAAUCAAGACAGUCAAUAUAAUCAUUAUAACAGAUAAAUAGGUCAAUGAGACAGAACAACACCCAGGCCUACUCAUCUAUGGCCACUACUCAUUUAUGGCCAAUUGACUUUUGAUAAAUGUGCUGAGGCAAUUCAACAGGGAGAGAAUAACCUUUUCCACAAGGAAUGCUGGGUCAUUUGGACACCCAUAAGCAACAAAAUAAAACAAUUACAAAUCCUCAAAACCCUUACCUCACACCACAUACAACAAUUAACUUUGGGCUGGAUGCAGUGGCUCACACCUGUAAUCCCAGCACUUUGGGAAGCUGAGGCAGGUGGAUCAUUUGAGGUCAGGAGUUCAAGACCAGCCUGGGCAACAUGGUGAAACUCUGUUUCUACUAAAAAUACAAAAAUUUUCUGGGCAUGGUGGCAUGUGCUUGUAAUCCCAGCUACUCAGGAGACUGAGGCAUGAAAAUUGAUUGAACCUGGGAAGUGGAGGUUACAGAGAGCCAAGACCACGCCACUGCACUCCAGUGUGGCUGACAGAGCGAGACUCCAUCUCAAAAAAAAAAAUUGUAAUAGGUCAUAAAUCUAAAUGUGUGAACUAAAACAGUAAAACUUGUAAGAAGAAGAUAAGAUAAAAUCAUGGUGACUUUUAGUUUGGGAAAGGUUUUUUAAAUAGAACACAAAAAGUUCAAACUACAUGAAAAAACCAAUAAGCUAAAUUUUAUUAAUUUAAAACUUUUGCCCUUUAAGAGACACUAUAAAGAGGCAAGCUGCCAAGCUGGAGAAAUUAUUUGCAAACCAUGUUCAAAAAGGACUUCUUUCUAAAACAUGUCAAGAAGCCUUUCAACACAAUAAUGAGACAAAACAAUUCAAUUAAAAAGUAGGCAAAAUAUUUGAAUGGAUAUUUCACCAAAGAAGCUAUAUUAACAGACAGAAGCACGCAAGACGAUGCUGACAACCAUUUAGUCCUUAGGGAAGUGCAAACGAAGACCAGUAUGAGAGGUGCCUACAAACCCACCAGCAUGGCUAACAUGUUCAAAAGUGGCCCUGCCAAGGGCUGGCGAGGAUGUGGGGCAACUGGAGCGCGCAGCAUGUUGGCAGGAUCAUAACACAAGAACCACAGGGAACGGUUCGGCCAUUUCUUAAAAAGCUACACAGAGUCACCAUGUGACCCAGACAUGUCUGUUCUGGGAACGUCCACAGAAAGACUGUGUCGUAAACGUUCACAACAACCUUGCCUGUAAUCACCAAAAUCCAAAACAACCUGAACGUCCUCCACGGGUCAGUGGAUGAACCAAUUAUGAUACACCCAUGCAACUAGUGCUCCCCAGCAUUGAAAGGAUGAAUUGUUGGAUGAAUCUCAAAAUAAUUACACUGUGAGACAAUGUCAGGCAAUAAGAGUAUACACGCUGUGUUACCCAGGACAGAAAUGAAUUAAUCUACAGUGACAGAAAGGUCAGUGUCAUCAGAGGAGCAGGAGGGUGGAGGGACGGGGCAGGGGCCAGCCUGGGGGAGGGGAUGUCCAUGGUCUCGAUUGUGGUCAUGGCUCUGUGGGUGCAGCAGAAUGUCAAAACUUAUCAAACCGUACGUCUUAAAUAUGGGCAUUUAAUUGCAUGUCAAAAAAAUCUAAACAAAGCUGAAAAUGGACAAAAUACCACAACCAAUGACAUCUGACCGUAAAGAGAUGGAUUUAGGUAGAAGGAAGAAUUCUUUAACACAGAAUAUGGGUCUCUGAGGGAAAUGUUAUCUCGUAAUUUUCUCACUUUUGGUGUAUUUAAGCUGUAGGACAAGGAGUGAACCCUAACAUUUGGUGAGAGUCUGUGAAACACACUAGGAACCCCCAUGCUGCUUGCGAGUUACUUCCGAGAAACAGCAGAAUGUCACACCCUGUCACCCGCAGGUGCCGUCUGAGGGGCGCUCAUCCCCACCAGCCCGAGGGCCUCCCCGCCAAGGGAGGGGUGUACUCCCUUCCACUUGGCGUCUGCUUGUGCAUUGCCCCUCCCUGAACUCAAGACCUGAGCCUCUCUCGCCUGGACUAUUUGGAAAGUCUACAAAUGGAAGAAGGGGUGCUCUCACUGAGUUGUGUCCGCACAAGGGAAACUGUCCAGGAGCCACAGAAGCAACCGCAAAGUGAGCCUCUCAGACGUGGUUAAAGGGAAGCCAGGCAAAAAGACUGCACGCUGUUGGGUUUCAUUUACUCAAAACCCUAAAACAGGCAGAAUGAGUCAUCUGUGGUAAACCAGCAUUGGGGUUACCUCUGGGGGCCGGGAGGGAACCCUGGGGUGCCAGUCACGUCUGGCGUCUCGGCCUGGGUGGUGGGGAUGGCUCGCCAAGCCUGUUUGUUGCACACGUGGCAUGUCAGCAGAAACACGGGGCAAAUACACACGUGAACACAAGAACCCCGGGUCCCUCCCUCAUCUACCCAGCGACCCUCAGUCACCCCAGCCGGCUCCCUCUCGCCACCCACGGGCUUUCUGUGGAGGCCCCAGCCUGGCCCUGGAGGCCGUGACCCACCCCGCCUCUUGCCUGAGGUCAGCCCAAGAGACCUUCCUGUCUUCGGCCUGGAGAAGGAGCGGCCGCCAGGACCACCCGGGCCUCAGCUCCCUGGGAGGGCCCCUGGAGGACCGGGGCUGCUAAAGUCCACGGGCAUCACCGCAUCUAAUCCAGGCCCUUUGAUGUGGGUGAUGUUGAUACUCCCACUUUACAGGUGGGGAAACCAAGGCUUCAGCUUCCGUGGCCAGGGGAUGAAUGGGAGUGUGGUCUGGAUGGUGGCUCCUGGACCGGAAGCAUGAUGGGAGCCAUGAGGAAUGCAGGUUCUUGGGUCCUUCCAGCUCUGCUGGAUUGGAUGCUCGUGGGGGCUCAGGGUCAACACAACCCCCCAGGACUCUGACCUGGGAAGUGGAGCAGCCUGAUUUGGAGGCGAGGACACACCAGGAGGCACCUUGCCCUGUGGCCACUGCACUGAGGCUUGAGAGAUCACUAGAGACAGCUCAGCCUCAGUGCUCCCGCGCCCCCGCCUCGGUGCUCCUGCGCCCCCGCCUCGGUGCUCCUGCGCCCCCGCCUCGGUGCUCCUGCGCCCCCACCUCGGUGCUCCUCCACUCCCACCCCGGUGCUCCUUCCACCUCUGCCUCACCCGAUGGACUGUGCCUUUGCGUUUCUUGUGCACAAAUCCUGCUGAAGUCUGGGCAGCUGUGUGUUUGAUGAUGGGCUUGUAGGAGAGAAGCAUCUGGACUGCGCCGUGCAGAUGGCGCUUCUCUCCAGGCACAGUCACAUUCCUGGGAGGUUCCUGGAGGCCUCCGAGCCUCGUGCAGACCCAAGGCUGCCUCACCACCAUGGCCACAGCCCAGUGCUGGCUGCCGGGCAUCAAAUCUGCAGAAAUGCACGUGGCAUAAAAGCACCAGAGACAUCCGUCCAGAGCCGAGGGCUCCUCCCUGGCCCAACAUUUUGUCCACGUAAGUCCACUUUUUGGCUGCUGCUCCCAGGCCUGGCAAGAACGCAGAUCCCCACAGCCUCCUGCUCCCUGGCAGCCUGAGGACAGUGUCGUAGGCCUGGGAUCCUCGGGCAGAACUGAAUGCAGCUUUUCCAUUGGAGGGCGCUGGGCCCACAUGGCAAUCACAGGUAUGGCAGAUGAACUCACGGGAUGCUCCGGGACUCCAGGGGCCUCAGGAGAAAGGCCCACUGGCAGCGGGUUGCCCAGGGCUCCAGAGGGGGGCUCCAAUGUGAACCAGUUGCUUGUGGCACAGCGGGUCACCCAGGAUGGCCCUGCGUGGUCAGUGAUAACAGGCAGUCACUCACAGCGCGACUUCACCCAUGGUCACUCCCGGUGACCAGCACUGCACAGCCUGGGCUUUCGUCCCACAUGGCACCUCCCUGUCCAGCCUUGGCCCAAGUGCCUGGGAAACAGACAGGGCACCGUGUGCCUGAACACACUCGGACAGUCGAGGCCCCCAGGAGAAGCAACAGGCAAUGACUCGGUCCCCAAGAAGCUGAGCCUGUCCUUGCUGGGGUCUGUCAUCUCCUCUUAGCCCCGCCAGGCUCCUGAAGCUGCCACAUGUGCAGCGGGAGGUGGGUGGUUUGGGAGCAGAGCGAGGCUCUGGAUGGACGGGCUUUACCACCAGCAGCCACCACCACCUGCUCUGCAGGGCCUGGGCCAGCCCUGAGGAGGUGGCAGACGGAAGGAGGGGCAGCACUGCCUCAGGUCUCCUUUACUGUCUUCCAGACAUCAGCUCAGGGAGAGUAGGCAUGUAGCACUGAGAAACAGGGUUGCUCCCCAUGGCUGCCUCUGCUUCCCUGCCGCACAGUGUCUGUACACGGCCUGGGGACCUGCGAGGCCAGACCGCAGGGCAGGGGCCCACGGCUGUGCCAGCUUCUCUCCCAGGCCGUGGCGGUUAUUACCUCCUGACUUGGCAGAGCAUCCGGCUACUGGAGCCCAUUGGUUCCGGCCAGUGCAGUCAGGACUUAGCUUCCCAGCUGUGAUCUAAAUCCCAGCCUCCCAAAGGCACAGCGCCUAAGUUCUCCCCUGCCAAGCUCACAGCCUUCUCCUUGGCAGGCUGCCCUUUCUCCUGCUGGACCAAACCAAGGAGCACGGUGACCCAGGGACACCACACUCGGUGUCAGCCUCUGAGGCCAUGGAGCCACGCAGACCCAGCACAGGAUUAGAAACAGACCUUCCCGGGAGGCAGAGAGCCAGGCCUCCUGGUUUAUAGCAUGACAAGGCAGCACUCAGGAGGACGCAUCAAUCCUUCUCCAUGUCAGCACCUGUGACUGUGACCACUGGUGAGGUGGACAUGCUUCUUUUUCCAUUUUACAGAUGAGGAAACUGAGGCCAAGGGAGGGUCAGCAGCCUGCCCUGGGCUGACUGGUGAUGCAGCGAGGGUGGGGUGUGGGAGGGUGGCGGCGGCCCUUGCAGUCCCUGGGAACCUGCACCUCUUCCUGGGCGCUGUUCCCCUCUCUCUCCCAGGACCCUUGGGCCUGGCGUUUCUUCACCUGCGACCAUCCAGGAGCUGGACCUGCCCUAGGGCGUCAGUUUCCAGGGAAGCCUCUGGCCUGUGUGUGAGCCUCCCCACCUGCCCGGCCACGGCCUCCACAGGCGCCCUGCGCAGCCCCGCCCCUCCUGGGGCAAAGGCUUUGCGAAGACUUUCUUCUCUGGCUCAUCCCUUUAAGGAGGCAUAAAAACGAACCCCGGGCCUCACAGGUCCGGAAUGCGCCCCCCUCCACGAUGGGAGCUUCUUGGCCUUGGCUGUGCAGGGGCCGCGGCUCCUGGGGGUCUGGCCGGAUCUGCAGUAGUGCUGAAUGAGCUGUGGCCAGGAAGACGCAAUGAAUAAUUGUCACUUAAAAGGAUAAACAGAAAUUCCAUUUCCCUUUUAAAUACUUGAACAUUUCAAAACAUCUGGAGGACGCGAUGCUUUUCCUUCCAAGCAUCUCCGUGGAGUUUUGUGGGUUACCGCAGAGGAUCGGCAGCAUUCCUCUCUCAGGGAAAACUGGCCUGAGCAUUGCAUAACGCAGGCAGACUGCACCCCUCACGUCGCCUGGGGCCACAUGCACAUGUUUCCAAGAGACUUGCUGGAGAAUCUUCCCCGGAUCUUGACAAAGUUGGACAUGGAAAGCACGUUGGUCCAUCCAAGGUCCACAGAGCGACCCUGGCUAUGAAAAAUCAUCCUCCGAGUGGGAGUCUGUCUGCCAGGAGUGAGGUGACACCGCACAUGGCCUCAGGAGCUGGAAACGCUGGUGAAUUCAGAUGCAGCCAAAGCUUCUAACUUAGUCACAGUUAUUAAUUAUUCUUGGUCUUAUUGGAGCAGGAACCACUGCCAUGCAUCAGGCCAGCAAGGCUCACUCCCCACCGUAGGAUCCCUGUGUAGACGGUCGCUCCAUCAGUGUAGUUGGGUGUGUGGAGCAAGGGACUGGGCUGACCCUACCUUCCAAGCAUCGAUGUGGCCUUCAGCAGAGCAGGAGGAGAUAGCCCAGGACUUGUACUUUGCAGUUGAAGUGCCAGACCUAAGAAAUGCAAACCUGAGGAUGGAAAGAGGGUGGAGAGGGGGGAGGUGUCUGGAUUGGCCGUCCAGAGCAGCCCCAGCUGCAGCAAGUGGAACUUGGCUGGCUGCCUCACAGGCCUGGUGGCAGCGUCCCCAGCGAGGAGCCUGUCCCACAUAUGAAGGUCCCCAUACCCUUAGCCCCUAGCUGAGAGUUUCACUGACCAGAGCUCCCUGAGUCCAGGGCUCCACUCAAGGGACUGCUGUCCCCGUUGGUGAAGAAGGCCUGUUGGGGCCAAUGCUUCCCCCCACAGGGAAGCGGAGCUGUAUUUUGUCGGACAGAACUUUGCAAGCCUGAAACAGCUGGUGGUGGCCCCAGAGCCAAGAUCUGACCUCACUCCAGAGUUGAAGGGCACAGAGAAGGCACAGCUAGAGGCGGCAGGUACCCCUCAAAGCUCUCGGGAGAGGGUACAAAGUGGGACCUCCCAGCACCCUUGGCCUCCAGGCCUCAAAAGCCCUGAGAGGGCUGCAUGCAAGGAGACAAAGCUGGAGAAGGAUGUGGGAGGCAGGUGGCUAAGAAGACAGGCUGGAAAGGGACGUGGGAGGUAGGUGGCUUUGCUCUAAACAGAAUCGUCUCAGUAAUGUGACACUGCACAUGUAUAGGUAGGCUCGCUCAUGGGCAUAACCCUCUAAAACACACCUUUUAUGGAGUGAAAUUCACUUAACAGCCAUCUUGAAGCAUAUACUUCGGCGGCAUUUGCUGGAUUCACGACGUUGUGCAACCUCUGCUUCUCCAGUUUCAGAACAUUUCAUCCCUCCAGAACAACAGCUCAUCCCCAUUAAGUAAUCACUCCUCAUUCCUUCCCCAUCCUCUGGAAACCACAGAUCUGCUUUCUGUCUCUAUGGAUUUGUCCGUUUUGGAUAUUUCAUAUAAAAGGAAUCACGCGGUGUGCGAA